CGUCCGGCGGCGGCGGCAGCGGCAGCGGCAGCGGCGCUGAGUUUUGUCUCCCGGGCCGUCUGGGCGCGCGCGGGUGUCCCAGAAUGAAAUAUGACUGAGGACUCUCAGAGAAACUUUCGUUCAGUAUAUUAUGAGAAAGUGGGGUUUCGUGGAGUUGAAGAAAAGAAAUCAUUAGAAAUUCUCCUAAAAGAUGACCGUCUGGGAAUCUUGCCUCCACACCACGAGUCCCAUGCCAAGGUGAUGAUGUAUCGUAAGGAGCAGUACUUGGAUGUCCUUCAUGCCCUGAAAGUCGUUCGCUUUGUUAGUGAUGCCACACCUCAGGCUGAAGUCUAUCUCCGCAUGUAUCAGCUGGAGUCUGGGAAGUUACCUCGAAGUCCCUCUUUUCCACUGGUUAGUGGUCACUUUUGUCUGACACUAAGCUCAACUCUAGACCGUCCCAUCUUGCCGGCCUUUGAUUACAUCAUGUUUUGCCUUAAAAACUUUUGGUGGCUCCCUGUUGUUAUUAGAAUAAAAGUGACACAUCUUUACUUGGCAUUCAUGGCCAUGCACAUUCUGACCCAACCUUCUUACUUUUUGUUUUUUUAAAAUACGUUUUAUUUUGAAGUAAUUUCAAACUUCCAGAAAAGUUGCAAGAAUACUACCAAGAAUUUGCAUAUACCCUUUACCCAGAUUCUCCAGUUGUUAACAUUAUGCAACUUUUUUCUACAUCCAACAUUAUUUAAAAAGUUAAAAAAUAAAAAAUUGUAGGUGCUAAGUAGCUUUAAGCAUCUGUUUUGCUUUGUGUGCAUCUGUUUUGCUUUGUUGUUUUAAAACGUAUUUUUUUAAACACAUUUUUUUUUUCCUAAAUCAUUUGAGAGUAAGAUGCAGACAGGAUUCCCUAUUACCUCAGAUUCCUUCAGUGUACACUUCCUAAAGACAGGACACCCCUGUAGAUAGCCAUAGUACAGUCCUCAAAACUAAGACAUUAACAUUGAUACAAUAUUAACGUAAUCUACCAGCUCCAUUUGAAUUUCACCAAUAAUGCCUUCACAAAUAAUCAAACGGUCAAAGUUCUGGGUGAGGACUGGAUCCUGGUUUAGGCAUUGCACUGGGUUAUCAUAUUGCUUUAGUCUCCUUUGACUUGGGACAGUUCUGUCUUUUUUUAUCUUUCAUGCCUUUGACAUUUUUGAAGGGCAUAAUCAGAUGCUUUGAAGAAAGCCCCUCCCUUUAGGUUUGUCUGGUGUUUCCUCCUGAUUAGAUUCAGGUUAUUCAUUUUUGGCAGGGAUACCAAGUAGGUGAUGCUGUGUCCUUCUCAGUGUCUCUUAUCAGGAGGCACAUAGUGUGAAUUUGCCCCAUAAGAGGUAGUGUUAACUUGGAUCACUUGGCGAGGGUGCUGCCUGCUGGAGUUUUCCGCUGGAAAGUUUUUACUUUUCCCUUUGUAAUUGCUAUUUCUCUUUGUGGGGAGACACUUUAAAACUGCUAUGUAAACAUCCUAUUCCUUAUUAAACUUUUGCUCAUGAGUAUUCUCAUUUGACGAUUUCUAAAAAAUUUUUAUUUUUUAACUUUUUAAAUAAUGUUGGAUGUAGAAAAAAGUUGCAAAAAUAGUGCAGUGUUCUGAAAUACCUUCACCCAGUGUCCUCAAAUGUUACAUCUCAUACAACCGUAAUGUAAUGAUCAAAACCGGAGAAUCACAAUACUGACAGCUACUCUGUAGGCCUCACUGGGAUUUUGCUGAUGUCCCACUGAUGCUCUUCUUCUGAUCCAAGAUCCAGUUCCGGAUCACACAUUACAUUUAGCUGCCACGUCUUAGUCUUUAAUCUGGAAGAGUUCUUUUUUUUUUUUUUUUUUUCUUUUUUUUGAGACAGAGUUUUUCUCUUUUUGACCAGGCUGGAGUGCAGUGGUGCGAUCUUGGCUCAACGCAACUUCUGCCUCCUGGGUUCAAGCAAUUCUUGUGCCUCAGCCUCCAGAGUAGCUGGGAUUACAGGUGCGCACCACCACUCCCGGCUAAUUUUUGUAUUUUUAGUAAAGAUGGGAUUUCUCCAUGUUGGUCAGGCUGGUUUUGAACUCCCGACCUCAGGUGAUUCACCUGCCUUGGCCUCCCAAAGUGCUGUGAUUACUGGCGUGAGCCACUGUGCCUGGCCUGGAACAGUUCUUCAGUCUUUGUCUUUCAUGACCUUGACACUUUUGAAGAGCCCUGGCCAGUAGAGCAUUUCUCAAUUUGGGUCUGUCUCAUGUUUCUCCAUGAUUAAACUCUGGUCACGCAUUAUUGGCAGGAAUAUCACAGAAGUAUGGGACUCAUUACUGUGCUGCUAACUUUGAUCACUUGGGUAAGAUGGUGUCUGUGGAGUUUCUCCACUGUAAGGUUACUAUUUUCCUCUUUGUAAUUAAUAAAUAACUGUGGAGAAGUACUUUGAGACUUGUAAGUAGCCAUCCACUAAUGAUUCUUGCCUGAACCAAUUUUUACUAUGCUGAUUGCCAAAUGGUGAUCUAACUCCUUCAUUCUUUCUGCAUGUAUUAGUUGGCAUUCUUCUCUAAGGAAGAGUUUUCCCUUCUCCUUCUUUAUUUAUAUCAGUAUGAAAUUAAAGUGUUAUUUGUUUGGCUAAAA